UGAACAUAUAUGUUUUCUCCUGGACCUCUGAAUUACUAAGUUAUUUUUCCCACUUUUAAUAUCUGAAAUAAAAGGGUUGGGUAUUUGCAUGGGGUGUGAGAGAAAUCAAUGUUGAUUCUAUAUUUAAUAUUUUUACCUUUUAGCAGUUGAGAUUUUGAAUGGAACAUCAUAUUCCUUAUUGUAAAAGUAAGAUCAUAAUUAAAAAGCUAGAUGCAUUCAUUAGGCAGAGUUUCUUUAAACCUAAGUCUCUUCAUCUCAUCUUAAUCAUUAUAUUACAAAGUAGGCAUUUCUGUCUGCCUAGUGGCAUGUCUUGCAAAAGAAUGAGAGAGUUUUUGAAGGCAAGAAGAAGAAGGGGGCCAAUUAUCGGCUUUUGCUUCCCUGCCACCUGCCAGCGCUUUUCCUUUUAAUUAAUGAUCUGAUGUUACUGGUCAAUAUAAUAAGAAAUGCUUGUACAGUUGGGGUCAGAAAAUUCUGGCUUUGAUCUCCCUCAACUUUCUGAAACAUUUAUUUGUUUUCUCUAAAUUAUUUCAGUUUUAUUUUAAUCUUUUCUAUCCUGCUGAGGGCUGCAAGAAUGAAAACCUACACUGUUUGUCAUUUGCUUUGGCAGAGCAAAGACUGCUUACUUAGAAUUCUAUUUGUAAAUUAAACUGCAAACCCAGUUUGUCAUAAAAGACAUCUGAUCCUUUUGAAAUGACGAAAACUGUCUUUUGUCUGUAAAGGCUGAUAAAUUAAGUGCCAGUUCUCUUCUGGUCUUUGAUCUUGCGGAGGGUUGUGUGUGUGUGUGCGUGUGUCUGCAGCUUAUAAUGGGACAUAUUCUGUAUGUCACGUUAAAUAGUCUCCAAAAGUGCAUUAUUUUUGGCCUUCAUAUUCCUUAGUACAGGACAAAAAUGCAAACUAGUACUGUUUCUGUAUAUAUUUUAAUGGCUACUUAAAAAUAUCUUUAUAACAUAGUUCUAAGUUAAAAUAACUUCCUUUUUAAAAAAACAAAGCAUUUAUUCUUUAUAUGGAUAUUAAAAUUUGGGAAUAAAAAUGCCUUCAGAGCAUAUUUUUCUGUAAUAUUGAACUACUUUGAAAUCCAUUAUUAAGGAGUUUGAGAAAGUGAAUUUAAAAAUCCUAAACUCAAAAAUACACUAAUACCAGCCUUGAUUGUCCUUCUGUCUAAUGAUAGGAAAAAUAUGAUUUUAAAGUCAAAAUCAGAUUAUUUAUGCCCAUAAUACCGUAAAAUACUUGCUGACCUUGAGACAUAUUAAAAUUCAACUACCUUAUCUUACUGUAGUAAAACUUAUGCUAUGAAUGUACAAAUCUAAUCCUAGGCCAGUGAAAAAUUACAUCUUUUUAGCUCAUUAUAACUAGAUUACCUCAUUAUAAAAUUUUUGCAAAAACAAAAUCACAAAGAAAUUAUUAGAGUUACUCAUUUAAAAACUAAUCAAAGUAUUAUUCAAUGGAUAGAGAAAUAAUUAUGAAAAUAGAAUCCCAACUUUUAAGAAUGCUUUCCUUAUAUGCAUGUACUUCCUACCGUUAAUGCCUUAGGGAGAAAGAUUGUUAAAAAGAGAAAGAAGAAAAAAAAGAGAAAGAAAUUCAGCUUUUCUGUACGUGAUAUUAAAAUUUUUAUAGGCAGCUUCAAUCAAUGAUAGAUGAUUCUUGAAAAAAUAAUCUUUGAAAUUUUAUUUUUUUGAUGGGUGAUUCUUUUUUAAAUUGAAAAGUACUACUUUCCUAGUAGAAUUAGUUUGAUGAUUAGAACAUUUAUUUAAAUAUAUGGAGAAGUUAAAUAAUAUUUCACACAUGUAAGUAUUUAAAUAUAUGGAGAAGUAAAUAAUAUUCACACAUGUAAAGGCCUGAAUAUAUAAAAUGACAGAAGAGACUAUCUUGUUAUUUACUCAUAAAUGACAAUAUAAACAUAACUGAAAUAUUUAAAAAUAUAGAUAAAAAUUAUACUGAAAGGUGGUGUAGAUUGAUUAACUAAAUAUAUGCUUGAAAUUCAGGGACACAGACUUAUAAAGAAAUUUAAAGAAUAGACAAAUAAAAAUAGUUCUGAGAUGGAGCUAGGACCAUUUACUGAAAGUGUGAGAUGGUUUAAAGUUAUAGUAAUUUUCUAAAAAUUUUUUGGGUGAUUUUUAGAACCCAUUUCUAAUAAAUAUAGCUUUUUCAUCAGUUUUCUAAAGUUAUCUCUUACAAUUUUGGUGGAAAUAGGAUGAAGCAUCACAUCAUAUUUUAGAAGCUCCCCUGCCCCACUAGACAGAACAGGACAAUUGUAAAUGUCUUAAAUGAGUUGUGUUAAAAUCACAAAUGAUCUUACUAAAAUUUUUUGUGUGUGAUUUAAAUUGAUAAAAUAUACUUGAAACCUGAAAAAUGUUACUAUUAGUAUUGUUUGAUUGUUUAAUAGGUUAACUGAGAUUUAAUUGGGGGGGGUCCUUUUAAAAUCCUUCACCAAAGCAUUUAAAUUAUACUUACAGGCUGGUUGACUUUCUAUGCAUGUGUACUCUAUUAUUGUGUCAGAUUGACCAGUGGUCUUGGCUGUUCAAAGGUCAGUGGUCACAGUUGUCCUGAAUUACUAGUUCUUUUUUCCUGUGGACCCUCUGCUGUGUUGCAUGCUGUAAUCUUCUUAAUGGCUUCAUUCCAAUAUUCACACAUAAUAUUUUAGAUUUAUUGACUGUUAGAAAUACUACCAUGCCAGUAGCAGUUCCGCUACUCUUAAGGUAUUUAAAAUUGGAAAAAUAAAUCAGGGCAAAGCUUUCAGGAUUCCUUUGUUUUCGUUAAGGGAGGGGGAAAACCUCUUUUCCUGUCUUCUGACAAGAACACUUGUUUUUUGAUUUCAUCAUUUCACUAUAGAUUUGGAUCAUUAAAAGAAAAAAAAACAUAUUUUAUUGGGAGUGAUUUUAAUGAUAUUGAUUAUUACAUGGAAUAACUUUUAAAGGCAGUAGAUCCAAUAAAAUAUACUCUUGUAGUUUUUGUCUAUUAAUAUAUUGUGACUUUAUUUUUUAGUGGCUGUGCCAAAUAGACACCUUCAAACAUCUGUAGUAUAGUUUGAAUGUUUUGAAAUAAAAAAAAGUAAAUGUUAGGACUCAGUUACAGCAUCAAUCACAGUUAGUGUUAUUGUAGUAUGUUUAUAAGGGUGAGAAAAAGAACCAAUUGAAUUAAAUAUAACAUUUGAAAUCUCAAAUGACUUGAUUUUAAUUUAUGAAAAUGCAGUAUUAAAACCUCCUAUUCCAAAUCUAUAUAGAAUUUAGUUUUAAUUGCAUAAUAAUUUAAAAUAUAUUUCUGAGAUAUUCCUGCUCAUUUUAAUUUUUAUCAUUAACGUUUUAAAAAAGCAAUUUGGAGGUUGUUACUAUUUCAAAUAUAAAUAGAAUUACUCUCUUACUAGGAAUUAAGCUAAUAAUUAGAAUUAUAAUAUUUAGGAAUUCUCUCAUAUGAAUAUUAAACAAUUGUAAAUUCCUAUAGAUGAAAGCACAUUAGAAUUGACAUCUGAAAAGGUUACAUGUAUUAGAAUAUUCAUUACAACAGGCAAGUUUUUUUUUACCUGUAUUGCUUAACGGUCUCUAAUAAUUUAAACUUAUUAGAUUGUAAGAAUAGUAAUAAUAUUGAUAGGUCAAUAUGCUAUUCCUAUUUUAGAUAAGAAAAUCAAGGCACAGAAAGUAUACUGUUAAUGGUAUAUCUAUAGAUUCAGUUCAUAGAGGUUGAUCCUCAGGCCUGUGCCCGAAACAGUAGACCAUGGUCCCUUUCAUAUAAAUGUGAUAUACAAUGUAAUGAAUAACUCAUUUAAAAUAUAUUAUAGAAGCUUACUUGCCACUUAAACUUGUUAAAGAAAUAUCAGUUUGAUCCAUUUGAUUUAAAUUAGGAUUUUCAGCACUAUUUUUAAAACUUCAUUUUCAUCUUAAAUAUAAUACUAUUGGAAAAUGAUUUUCUGUUUUCUACUAUGAGGGUGUAUAGAAAAUAUGGUACACUUAAGAGUUAUUGUACAAGUCACUGUAGACCACUGUAUGUUACAGGAUAGCUAUAUUUUGUAUGAAGCAUAUUUAAUUACUAAAACGUUGAAAAGACCUUAUUAUAAUGAUGCUAUCUAAAAUAUCAUACAUAUUAUGGUGAAGCUUUCAGGAAUCAUAAGAAGGAGUGCAUUAAGUGGUUUUAUUGUGAUAAAAAAAGGAAAGACACAAAUUGCUCUGAAUCACCAAAAAUCAUUAAGAGCAUGUAAGAACUGGAGAAAACCUCUAAAAUUCUGAUAUCAAAUAUUUGAAUAUCUACAUUCAAGUGAAUUUAUUAAUUUGGGGAUAAGUUUGAGAGAAUUAGUUUUUUCAGGGAAUUCUAAAAUAAACUUUUCAAAAAAUAUUAAGUUAUGUAAGCAAAUUAAACUCUUAGAACCACACAGAUUGUCAAUGGAUAUGUUUAAUUCAUUGAAUAUUUCCUGUAAUCUAACAUGAAGGUUUAACAUGUUAAAUUGUCAUAAUAUAUGUUAUAAAGAAAAAAAAGGGCCCCAGAGAAUAUUAUAUUAGUUCCAGGUUUGCCACAGUUCUGCUGUAAUCUUUAUUGUGUUUAAUGGUAAAUGAAGUCCCUAACAAAUUUCUAGGGUGGUCAGGUUAGAAAGAUUCAUUCAGCUUCUAGAGUAACUUGGAGAACAUUUUAUUACUUCAGGAGACAAAUAUUGCUUUCAGUUUGCCCUUGGAAAAGUAUAGUCAUGCUUUUUCUCCUCUCAGUCUUCAAUUGUUAGAACUCAGGCAUCUAGGUGUACCUUGCCUCCACCACACAGCCUUGGUACUGUGCUUUGUAAAUAGGCAUUCAAUAAGUGAUUGCUGAAAGGAAAUAUAAUUACACUUCUUUUAUCUUUUGUAAUAGAAACUUGCUUUUAAAGUCUGUUUACAGUUACCUCCUAGAACAUUUUAUAAGGAUAUUUCCAUUUGACUUUAAUAAGAAUAAUGAAAAUGAGAAACCUGGACGUAUAUAUAAAGUAUACUUUUUGACUAUGAGCAUAACCUUUUAUUUCCUGUAUUUAGAAAAAGAGACCAUGUUGUGAUGGCAAUCAUUGUGCUUCUGCAUACCCAGCUGAAUGUCUGUGGAAACUCAGCUAUUCUUUUAAAUAGUUAUUAUCAGAGAUAUAAUUAUUUACAAAGUAGUUUUUUUGUUUGUAGGUAAACUAUUAUAGAUUUUGCUGUUCUCCCAACUGUUUUCUUGGUGUAUAUUUUGAAAAUAUAAACCUUAAAUGUUAGAACAAAGAAAACAAAAGCAAAACCCGAAAACCUUAACUGUGCUUGUAAACAUUUAAAAUAUUUUUGUUAGUUUCUCUCAAUUGAGUAAGAGAACCUGGCUUUCCCACAGCAAUGAUCCAGGCUUUGGUAAUACCCCCCUUUAUGUCUCUGUACUUCUGCCAUUCUAAAGUUGAUUUAUUGUUUGUUACUUUUAGUGAUUUUAAGUGCUCAAUGAAGUUCCUUGGCUUUCUCAUGGCUUUUCAUUUCCAACUAAAUUACCUAGCCUUUCUUUUAAUGUCUUCCUCCCAUGCUUCUUUCUCUUGUUACUGCAGAUAUUUUUUUUUUCUAAAAAAGGUAAACCUUGAUUUUGGCUGUUAAAAUUAUUUGCAAUUUAUUUCUGGUCCUUUAAAUUCUUGAUUUUUCCAUAUCCAAGCAACUUUUUGUGUGUAAUAUUGUGAGCACUGUCACAAUAGCAGUUCCCAAACCUUGCCGAUAUCAUAAUGACCUGGUGACCUUUUAAAUGAAUUAUGUUUCUGAGCACCAUCACAGAUACUUUGAUUGAGUCAACUGGAGGAAUAAAUGUAGAAUUGUGCAUGGAACAGAUUGUUAGAUUUGUUCAUUUAUUCAUUCAACAGGUAUUUAUCAAGUAUCUACUAUGUACACGCAUUGUGCUAAGAACUGGGUAUAUAGUGGUGAACAAGCAAACAUAUACCCUGAUUUCAUAGAGUUUAUGGUGUGUUAACACUCAUCUAGUAUUACAAAUAGAGACAAAUGUUAUAAAAGAACAGGGUGCAGUUGGAGAGAAUUACAGUGGUAUCCUAAUUUAGAUUAAGGGUGAGAUAGGUAGAGGCUGGACCUGUUGUAGCUCAGUGGCACGGGAAAAAAACCAUGUGUGUCUCUGUGGUGCAGCAAGGCAUUAUCUUAUGUGGUAGUGCAUAAAUUCUCGGGGGCUCAAGUGUUCUUCUCCAGCUUAAUAGUAAAGGUUGCAAGCCUGAGGUUUCAUUUUUCUUAUGACGUGGCAGGAACCUGAUGCUGUGCCAGUUGCACUGAGGAUGGGAUUUCAGGUGCACCAGUAUGAGAAAGUAUGGAAGCAGUUAGGAGCUUGGUCUAUAUUCUUAUUUCAUAUCUCUCAUAUAUCCUUUAUACUGUUUGUUUAUUAUCCUUUAUACUGUUUAUUAUCCUUUAUACUGUUUGGUAUAUUUAUUAGGGUACAAGCUAAGCUGCUAUAACAGAAAUACCUGAAUACUCAUUCUUAGAUCAAAAUAGAAAUGUAUUUCUCUAUUGUAUAACAAUUAAGAGGUAAGUUUUCCAAAGAUGUGGAACAACUCUGCCAUCCUCAAUACAUAGCAUCCAACUCUAGGUUUAAGGUAUGCUCUUUGUCUACCUUGCCGUAGAGUAAAGAGGAGAAUCCACAGAGGGGUAUUCAUAUCCCUUUUAGGGACAGCCUGAAAAUGUCAUGUUCCUCAACUCACAUUCCGUUUGUCUGAACCCAGCCAUACGGAUACAGCAAGUUCCAAGGGAUGUUGGAAACUAGCUGAGUUAACCUAGUUUUGUUAAAUAUGCACCAGUCCAAACUUAAGAUUUCCAUUAGCAAAGAAAGGGAGAAUAGAUGUUGGUGGACUUAAAGCCAUCUCUGCUGUAAGUAAACUGAUAAGAAAAUAAUUUUAGCCAAACUGAGAUGCCAUUUUUACUAGUCCGCACUCUCAGAUCAGCCUUUUGUGGUCCAGCCAAGCUCAGUGUAUCAGGAACAUCUUUCUGCAGAAUUGGCCUCAAUGAUGAUGAGUAUGAGUAAGCCAGAUGGGAGGAGGAAGAAGAGGGAGAGGAGAGAUAACAUAUAUAAAGGUUUUCCUGUGGGGAAGAGGUUGGUUAAUUCAAGACCUAUAUAGCUGUAGUGAAAUAAACAAAAGAAUUAUGCAAAAUGAGAUAGUAGAGAUAGGCAGGGGCGAUCAUAAAAGAUGUGUAGUUCUUGUUAAAGACCUUUGGAUUUUAUUGGAAAUUCAUUGUAUACUUGUAGAUGAUGCCAUAUUCGUUAGGAUUUGACAGGUACUUUAAACAUACAAUGAAACAAUGUAAUGAUAUGCUCUGUAGGUAAGUAUAUCAUAUGCUUUUCAUUUAAUAAAUGUUAAAGGUUACUGUUUUAAUCUUCGAAUAGAGACUUGUUAGAAAAUUAUUAAGAGAGAAGUGUUAAUUUUGCUUCUUAAUAAACUGAACUUUAGAAAGGUUAAAAAAGUGUAGGGAUUUAAUAUCUAAUUCAUGUGAUAACUAUAACAUGAUUCAAGGGAGAAUAAAAGUUUUCAACUUUAUAACUUUGUUCUACAGAUGAUUAUUUGACACUUUAACUUUUCUAAAUGUAUGUAGUUUUUAGAGAGCAGUUUAGUUAUAUGAAAGGAAAUAUUUAAAAAUAUCUUAGGAGUGUUUUAGGUUGUGUAGAUUAUCUAAAUAUUAUUUUGGAACACUUAUUUUUAUCUUCUCUUCUUUACCCUGAUGCUUCUCUUUGUGAUCAUUAAAAGUAAAAUAAAAAUUUCUAGGUAUAGCAGUUAAUAUAUUUUUACUGCAAAAGCAUAUCUAGAAAUCACAUCUAAAAGUUAAGUAAAAGAAAAAAUCUGUUACUUCUCAGAAAAACUCAACCCCCUUUUAUGCUCUGCCUUCCUGGCUUACUGUCCUUUGGUAUAAUUACUUCAUUACUUAGACUGAGUGCACAUGGCUUGCACUCUUUUAACAUGUACCUAUUUGCUGUGUUUACUUAUGUAAUUCUGUCCUUUUAUUCAUAGUCACUUUAGUGCUAAGAGGGUAAAAGUGGGGAAUUGGUGGUAAUAUUAUUCAUGCUGCAGUGAAUUCCCAGCGUGCUAAAAUCCAGGUUAUAAUUCUUCCCAUGGAUGGCUGCUUGGAGGUCUGAAUUCUCACUGAAAGGAAUUUAAAACAUUUGAUAAGAGCAAUGAAAUGAUGCUUAUUUCUGAAUUUUCUUUUCAUUGUUUAACUUUUCGUUUGUGAUCUAUCCUAAUACUAAAUUAGACUAAAAAAUGUAUUUACAGAGUGUAAAAUCUCUAAAGACAAUACAAUAAAAUGUCCUUUGUGAAGUAAUUCUUAGCCAUUGGAGGUUGAGGCUAGCUUGCUUUCUUAAGAAUAAAAAGAGAAAACAAUUGAUACUUUUUCAGUAUUAAUAGGAUUAUGUGAUAAUAGCCAUAUGACUAAGGCUCCAAAUGCUUUUCUGAAUUCAGAGUUAUGUGUGAGUAUAAGCCUUAGGAUUUCAUGGGAAGAGAUAUAUUUAUUUCAUAACUAAAGUUAGAAGUUUGGAAAUUAAAGCAGAAAAUGCUCUUUCCUAGACCAGGUAUUAAAAAGUACAGGACAGACCCCAUCAUUUUUAUAGAUAAAAACUGCUAAAAGCUAAUUAGCACUGCAAAGGGCAUUGGUAACUGGUGAUAAUUUACUCCAGUGAUGUAAAGACCAGAAACACAGCCAGGUUGAUGCAAUGAUUUUAUAUUAUAUUAAUAUCCUUAUAUCUAAAACUGAUUUUUAAAAAACAAUUGUUUUCUUACAGACUAUUUUUGAGCAUUCAUUUGCCCAUGUAGAAACACUUAGCUGCCCUUCUGGUCUCUGAAAAACAGGAACAACUUCAGAUGUACUGACAAUUGAAGCCCACUAGAGUAGGUCAAGGAAAAAUUAUUUUUAUGUAAUUUGUAAAAGUUGAAAUAAUGUAGAAAGAGGCAAAGGAGAAAUAUAACUAUAUUUCUUGCCAGGCAAUUUUAGUUUAAAAUCUGUAUGAAAUUAGAUAGUAUACUCAUGUAGAAUAACAUUGUCCAAAAUAAAAUGUGAGCCACAUGUAUGAUUGUGUUUUCUUGUAGCCACAUUAAAUCAUAAAAGAAAUAGGUGAAAUUAAUGUUAACGAUAUAUUUUAUUUAACCCUAUACCUAAAUAUUAUUGCUUCCAAAUAUAAUCAAUAUGAACAUUAUUGAGUUUUUUUUGUACUGAGUCUUCUAAAUACAGUGUCUGUUUACUCUUACGGCAAAUCUCAGUUGAGACAAGUCAAAUAUCAAGUGUGUAUAUGACUGAUAGCUACCUUAUUGGCCAGCAUAGUUCUAGAACAGGUACAUUCUUUUCCUAUUUUCUACACAUCCACAGGGAUCUCAGGAGCUAUCAUUGACUAGUUUUGGAAGUGAAGGCUGCAUAUUUAUGAUUUGGUUUGGAAUGGCUUGUGGCAUUGUGUUUAAUACUCCCUUAUAACUCAGGCAACAAUUAUGCAGUCAAGGAUCUGGUAUAAUAAAGGCUGAGGAAUGGCUUGACUUGCCUGUAUUCUUAGUGAGCAUAUGUGUUGUGAUUGUCCAGAGAACAUUGUGUUCUUGAUUUGUGGAGAACUGAGUUGUGAAUUUCAUGUUUUAUUUUUAAAAAUACACAUUAAGGAAUUUUCUUUUGCAGAGAUGUAAGGUGCAUUUUAAUUUUUUUUUAUUUUCUAAAGUAAAAAUCUUUUAAAAAAACUAUUUAUAUAUAAUAAUACUUUAAAAAGACUGGAAUCAUAUUCCUUACAUCGUAAUCUUUUUUGGGGGUGGAGGUAGUAAUUAAAUACGUAUAUUGAUAUGCACUCCCAUUGCUAUUGAAGGCAUUUGAAACUUAAAAGUAGCAUUAGAAGUUUCAGAAUAAAGGACAUUAAUUUAGAUUUAUUUUUGUAAUUAUUAUUGUUUGAAUAUGUGGGUUACCAAAAAAUAUGCAUUUAUUGAGAUUAGAUUUUAAUAAUAAAAAUCCCUCUUAAAUGAAUCCUGAUUUAUGCACUUUGUGGGCUAAAUGAAUUAGGCUCUCAAUUUUUAUCUGAAUCUAUGGAGCUUGGAUAUAAAUUGAAAAGAUCACAGCUAUGGGGAGAAGACCUACACUGCAAAGGCCUUUCUGCAUAGAUUAUGAACAUAACUCAAUAAUUUUUUCGAAACUGUGGUUAUAAUUGGACCCAAUGGGGGUCUGUUUCUUUGAUCAGAUCACAGUAACUGUGACUUUACACUGGAAAAUGUCACUAUUGUGAAGUUUUAUCACCUGUAGAGCUGGUCUUUCCUCUGAUGCUGUGUUCAUUUCUCAUUAGCAUUAUUCAAAGUUUAGUUGUUAAUUAGGUUGACAGUUCAAUUACAAUCAUAUACAAGCAAAGUCAGGGCUACUUGCAUAAAGAAAUAAAAAUAACCCUUCUUGCAUAGAUAUAUGUGUGCAUGUGUAUUUGUGUAUAUGUGUGCAUGUGUUGUGUGUGUGUAUAUGUGUGCAUGUGUAUGUAUGUGUGUAUAUGUUUGCAUAUAUAUGUAUGCACAUAUAUACCUAAAAAGGAGAAAUGACUAUUUUGUUAUAUGAUAGUUUCAUAAGGGUAAGAAUAUGCUCUGUUAAGUGAGCAUUCUUUCCAAAAUUUGUCGUACCAGUUUUUUUUCUAAAUAAAACAGAAUUGUUACACAACUUAAUAUGUUUCCAUUUUAAGCAUUGAUGAAUAUAUAUGAGAACCAAUAUUUUUAAGUGAACAGAAUAUAGUUUUCUAUUUUGUGUGAAAGGAAUUGGUACAGUGAAUUGGAUGCAUAGGAGCAUUUUAUAUCUCCUCCUCCUUAAAAAAUAAGAGUUUACAUCAGGAGUAUGAUCUCACUUAAAAUUCUGUUCAUAAAUAAUAUGCAUUUUCUAAAAUACAUAGCACUUAAAAGAUAGAAAAAUGUAUGAAAAAUUAAAACAAACUUAAAUAUCUUUUAAAAUUAUGCACAUUUUUAGGUAAGUUUUUCUUUGAUUUGAAACAUUAGUGUUUUAAUCUGAUUACCGGUUCAUGAGGCAAUGAUACUGAAUUCAAACCCACCAUGUGGUAGUGGAAAAAACUGGACAGAACUAGGUUUAGAUCCCAGCUUUGCCACUUAUUGGCUACAUAGUAAGGGCAAAUGAAUUCACAUCUUUGUUCCUCUAUUUCUUCAUUCAUAAAUGGGAAUAUGAAUGCUUUUCUUAGAAGACUGUGGUGAAGAUUAAAUGACACAAUGUAUAACAUUUGCAUAAAAUUCUCCACUCAUGGUAUAAUUUCAAUAACUUUAUCUCUUCUCCCCUCUUCUUUAUCUCAUAAUGACAAAAACUAUUCAACAAAUGACUGGAAAAUUAUAUAUGCAAAUGAGACUUCCAAAAAUAAAAUUAAAUGGUCUCGGCCUUGAAAAAUAAACUGAAGAAGCAGUCUACAGCUACGGGUGAUGGAGUAGCUAGGGCCUUUCUUAGAGCACAGGCUGCUUUGUUUGGAUCCUACAGAGAUGCACUGAGAUACAAACCUGGUGAGCCCAUCACUUUCUGUGAGGAGAGUUUUGUAAAGCACCGCUCAAGCGUGAUGAAACAGUUCCUGGAAACUGCCAUUAACCUCCAGCUUUUUAAGCAGUUUAUCGAUGGUCGACUGGCAAAACUAAAUGCAGGAAGGGGUUUCUCUGAUGUAUUUGAAGAAGAGAUCACUUCAGGUGGCUUUUGUGGAGGGAACCCGAGGUCAUAUCAACAAUGGGUGCAUACAGUCAAGAAAGGAGGUGCACUGUUCAACACAGCAAUGACCAAAGCAACCCCUGCUGUACGGACAGCAUAUAAAUUUGCAAAAAAUCAUGCAAAGCUGGGACUAAAGGAAGUGAAGAGUAAACUAAAACACAAGGAAAAUGAAGAAGAUUAUGGGACCUGUUCUAGUUCUGUACAAUAUACACCAGUUUACAAAUUACACAAUGAAAAGGGAGGAAACUCAGAAAAGCGUAAGCUUGCUCAGGCACGCUUAAAAAGGCCUCUUAAGAGCCUUGAUGGUGCUCUAUAUGAUGAUGAAGAUGAUGAUGACAUUGAAAGAGCAAGCAAGUUAUCUUCUGAAGAUGGUGAAGAAGCUUCUGCUUAUCUCUAUGAGAGUGAUGACUCUGUUGAAACAAGAGUGAAGACUCCUUACUCAGGUGAAAUGGACUUACUAGGAGAGAUUCUUGAUACAUUGAGCACACACAGCUCAGAUCAGGGGAAGCUGGCAGCUGCAAAGAGCUUGGAUUUCUUUAGAUCAAUGGAUGACAUUGAUUACAAACCUACGAAUAAAUCUAAUGCUCCUAGUGAGAAUAACCUGGCUUUCCUCUGUGGUGGUUCUGGUGACCAAGCAGAGUGGAAUCUUGGGCAAGACGAUAGUGCCCUCCAUGGCAAACACCUCCCUCCAUCUCCUAGGAAGCGGGUUUCCUCUAGUGGUUUGACAGAUUCUCUGUUUAUCCUGAAAGAGGAAAACAGUAACAAGCACCUCGGUGCUGACAAUGUGAGUGACCCUACUUCAGGACUGGAUUUCCAACUCACUUCCCCUGAAGUUUCCCAGACUGAUAAAGGAAAAACAGAAAAGAGGGAAACACUAAGCCAGAUUUCAGAUGAUCUGCUUAUACCCGGUCUUGGGCGGCAUUCAUCGACUUUUGUUCCUUGGGAGAAAGAAGGGAAAGAAGCCAAAGAGACUUCAGAAGAUAUUGGACUGCUCCAUGAAGUAGUGUCAUUAUGUCAUAUGACAUCUGACUUCCAACAAAGCUUGAACAUUUCAGACAAAAACACAAAUGGAAACCAAACUUAAAUCUUGCAUCCAAGCUUCUAUGGAGACAUUUUGAGAUUCAAUGCAAUCUGUAUAAUAAACAGAAUUAUUUGUAGGAAUGGCAACUCAUACUAUUUAAAUUUUUUUUUGCAUUUGCAACAUUUUUCUCACUUGUUCAUUUCGAGGAUAUAUGAAAUGCAUUGAUUUUUAAAUAUAAAGCGAAUUCUACUGUGCUUUUAAAUCAGGUACUAGUGUGUAUGUAUGUUUAAAGUAUGUAUUGACCAUGAGAUUUCCCAGUGUUUGGUGCUUAAUGCCGUUUAUUUUAUUUAAGCUAAGAAUGCAUAUGUAACCCAUGCACAUAACCAGUAGCUACUAUACUAAUCUGGUUGAGCAUGAACUGAUCAAGAUAUCAAAACUUAUCAAAACUAGCCUGAAGCUGAUGAAACUGUUAACCCACUAAUUGCCUUAAUCUUAAAGCUGUUUUUUAAGCAUACUUAAAUAAUGUAUGAAAGUAUGUAUAAAGUUUGAAGGAUAAGUUAUUAGUGUUCUGCAGAGCAAUAAUGCCUUUUUCUAUUCAUCAAAUCAAGGUCAAAAUUCAUCUUUUCAAGAUUAAAAAGCUCUCUUAAUGGAAAUAUUUAAUUUGCUUAUAUAAAGCACUAUAGCCAUGUUUUCCAAAAAGUAUAAAAAUAUACACUUACCUUUCAUUCAGUGAAAUAUAGGAAGUGCUGAAUUACAAUGUGAAGUUAAUGACUUCUGUUUACAAAUGAGACACUCUAACGAGUUUUCAGUCUCUCUGUAUGCCUUUGCUAUUUAGGGGUCCACCCCAAGAAAGCCAAAUACAACAUAAACCGUCCUGACAAAAAAAAAAAAAAAAAUCUUUUUUUAACUAAUAAUUCUCUAUCAAAAUGCUUCAUAUCAUCAUCUCAAAUUUACUUUUUAAAAUAAUUGACUUUGUAUUUUAGAAGUUUUAGAUUUACAGAAAAAUUGCAAAGAUAGUACAGAGAGUUCCCAUCUACCCCUGUUACUAACAUCUUACGUUACUAUGGUACAUCUGCCCCAAUUAGUGAACCAAUAUUGAUAUUCCAUACUUUAUUCAGAUUUUCUUAGUUUUCUCCUAAUAUCCAUUUUCCACAUCAAGAUCCUAUUCAGAAUACCACACUAUAUUGAGUUGGAAUGUCUCCUUAGGCUCCUCUUGCCUGUGACAGUUUCUUAGACUUUCCUUAUUUUUGAUGACAUUGACAGCUUUGAAGAGUACUGUCAGAUAAAUUGUAGCAUGCUCCUCUCUUGGAGUUUGUUGGGUAUUUUUUUCAUGAUUAGACUGGGAUUGUGGGUUUUGAGGAGAUGAUCACAGAAGUAAAGUGCCAUUUUCAUCAGGUCAUAUCAAGGGUACGUACUGUCAACAUGAUUUGUGAAUGCUGACAGGGACCUUGAUAACCUGGCUGAGGUAGCGUUUGUCACUCUAAAGUUCUUCCUGCCCUUUCCAUGCUGUCAUUUUUGGAAGGAAGUCACUACAUGCAGGAGUGAGGAGUCAUAAUUCCCCUUCUUUAGGGCAGAGAAGUAUCUACAUAAAUAACUGGGAAUUCUGUAUAGAAAAUUUGUUUCUUCUUUCUCAAAUUCACUGUUGAGCUUUGGAAUUCAUCUGAGAAGGAAUCAUGUACUAAUUACUUCAUGAUAGACUAGAUUACCAGGCACAAUCAGGGAAAAAAGCAGUGAUAGUAUGGUUAAAUUGUUAUUAGCAUUUUCAGUAUAUCCACUUUAUACAUCCCCAAUCAUGAUUUUUUUUACAUUUCUUUUUAGAAAAGAUGUUCAAGAAAUCAUUAAAGAACCCCAAUAAGACUAUAUUCUAAAUAUUUAUUGAAAGAAUAUAAUUUCAGCUAAAAUCCUAGAAGAGGGUUUGAAAUAAUUUAAAGAAAAUGACCAAGUUUUUUUAAAACCUACGUUUCAAAAUCUAAAUGGAUAUGUGUUAUUUGGGACACUUAUUCAUUAUGAUUAUAUAAGAAGACAAUUCUUGUUUCCCUUAUAAGUAUGGACUGUAUACAUUAAGGAAAACAAUGUUUAAUCCUUAUUUUUUAAUACAGAAGUCUCAAGGUUCUUGUCAAAUUUUGCCUUUAUAAGCUUAUUACAAAAUUACAACUUACUUUACUGAAGUUUAUAAUGGAAGAAGUCCAUAUAGCAAAAGAGCUGUUUUAAAUCAGAAGGAAAAAAGGUUACUCUGGUUGUUAAUCUGCUUGGCAAAUAUUCCUUCAUAAUUUGUGAAAAGAAUGCAAAUCAGCAUUUUAAUAUGAAUUUUGAAAUGAGGUAUGGUUUUUUGUUUGUUUUUUUCAGAACUCAGUCUGAAAAACAACUGUGAGUGUAGCAUGGGUCAAAUUUGGUUUUUAGUCCAUUUGCUUUAUCAACAUCACGGCUUCAGAAAUCCAAAUUUUGUUCUACUUUUCAGCCACCUUUCAAGGUGUUUGGUUAUAAUACUGUGUUGCUUUGAGGAUAUUUAGCCACUCAUAAAUAAUUGUCUCAAGGUAUUUAAAAGUGAUUUGUGCCUUAUUUUAAUGCAAAAUUAGCAGUUUUAUUCUAUUUUAAAAACAAAGGCAGAAAAACAAUUCUGCAUGUUAUUCUUUAAAAACAUCCAGAAUAAUACUACCAAGUAUUUGUAUUUCAAACCAGUAAAAUUUUGAAUAUUCAAAGUCUGCUCUUAAACUUAGACUUCCUAGUAUUAUGGUGGUUAUAGUGAGAAUGAAAUUAAACUGGGUGAGUUCCGAAAUAAAGGAAAGUGUUAUAUUCUACAGUGCCCAUAUUUUCUAUGGUAACUAAAUCAAAUAUUUGUAAGUUCCUCUGCUUUUUGAAAUUAUUUUUCAAAGAAGCAACACCUGUUAUACAACAGAAUUGUAUAAACUAAAAAGACUUUUGGCCUUGGUACAUAGUCUUUAUCUGGCCUGCAAUGGAGUCAUGGUUCUUUCUGAAUCCCACUCUCACUUUUUUCUUUUUACCCUUAGAUAUUGCAUCCGUGGUAUUUCAGGGGUAUAGAGAAAUAAUAUUGGAAUUUAGGAGCUAUUUUUUUAAGUGAAAAUAUUACUAAGUGGUAUCUUUUGAUGAUUACCUACUUUAAUGUGUCUUAGAAAAGCACCAAAACAUAGCAUGAUUAUUUUUUCAGUUAAUUAAAAUUAGUUAAUAACAUGUUCAUUUAAAAACUAUUCAUUGACUUUUUGUACCAGUCAUAUGCAGGGUACAGUAACUGAGGAUAUGGGAAAUAAAAUAACUGACAUAGUCCCUGCUCUGAAGGAACAAAGGAAAAGGAAUUGCAAAUUUUUAUUAAAAUAAUAAUAAUAAUAAUAAUAAUAAUAAUAAUAAUAAUAAUAAUGUGUUUUGCCUGGAAGUUAUUAGCUGAGAUUCUAACACACAAAAAGUUCAAAAAAAAAGAACAAAAACUGGCUGCUUAAUUUAAAGCAUGCUCUAAGUAUGAACCAUAGUAUCAUUUCUAAUUUCAUUAACUUUCUCAAUUAUUAUGCUAAGUAUAUUAUGCUGCUAAGAUACCCACAUUUAAGGGGCAGAUUUAGAGACUCUUUUAGAAACUGAGUGUCUUUAUCUUAUUAUCAGAUAACCAGGCUGCACAGGGCUCUCUAUAAUGGAAUGAUGCUCCUUUUCAAUACUUAGAGCCACUGUACUCAGUUUAGGAGUAACUGAAGGUGUGGAUGCAUGUUAAUGGGAAUCCAAUUUUUACUAUUUUUAUAUGAAUAACAGCGUUCUGUAGAAACAGUCUCUCCCUUCUAAAUAAAAACUAUGUGACUGCUGUUACUAGUGCUAUUCUAUGCGAAUAUCCUAAUAAUAGGAUUCAGGAAUUCUAAUGAAUUGUUUCUUAAUUAAGGUGAACAAGUAGACUCCUGAUCAAGAGGAGAACACUGUGAAUGUCUCAUAAUCAAUAGACCUUCAUUCUCUUGUAGAAAAUGUGGAUUUUCAGGAAAAGACUGAUUAUUUUCAUGAAUAAAUUUUCUUAUACAAAUUCCAUUUUGUUUGACAUAAAAGACCCUGAAUCUUAAGAUAUUUGUAAAUCAGAAUAUUUAAGAAUGUAAAAUGAAUCCCCAAAUCUAGUUUCCUCCAAAGCACUUCUUAAUGUAGGAAAUAGUUUUUACAAACCCUAUGUCAGUACUAAUGUUCCUGGGUCAAACCCAGUAAUAUUGUUAGUGUAUGUUGUUACACCUUAUUUAAGAGGCAGAGUGGUUUUGAGCAAGUCAGUUAACGUGAUUUGAUGAAGAAAUAAGGAAUUAUAUACAUUUAGACAGAAGAAUAUUUUAUUUUGAAAAUAGGAUUUCGUGCAAUAAUUUUUCUUGCAUAACUUAGUUCAUAUAAAUAUGUACAUCUGUUUUUCUGGCAGAUGCCUUAAGGUCAUGUUUUUCAGUAUUUGAGUAAAUCUGUAUGUAGCAAUGUUCUCAUUGAUUUCAGAAAAAAAUAUAUUCUUUAUAUUGUUGCCAGGAGAAAUGUUUUUGUUUAUUUAAAAUUAUUAUGGAUAUUGUGUUGUUGUAUCAUAACUAACUGCCUCAGCAACAAUAAAUAUGCAAUAAGAAAAUCCUGUACCUUAGAUUAGAUUGACAAUACUGUUACUUUAAAAGAAAUAUAUACGGUACAAAUUGCUGAUUCUACAUGUGUACAUUUAACAGAUACUCAGUUCUGCACCACCUAAAUCAAAAUGGCAUUUGUAUGCUGAUGAUUACAUAUGUGGAUUGUAGUAUCCUUUGUGAUGAAUCUUUGAUAAGAUUUAUAAAGGGCAUUGCCAAUACUUUUUGACUGUGUAAAUUAAUUUUUUGUAUGAUGUACAGUUUGUUUAAUCUUAGAGCUUCUAUAGAUUUCUACUUUAUUAUACUUGAAUGAGGCAGAAAAGCACUGUGGAAAAUCUGUAGCUCUGGAUGCAACAUGCAGACAUACCAAAAAAAUAAUAAUAAAGCAAGGUACUGAAGAGCAAUGUUAACAGAAUGCUUUAUAUCCAGAAUGCUAUGUUUUUUUCAAGCCACAUUUUAGUUGAAUGAAGUAAAGUUAUUCAAUCUUUUAUUUUAAAAUAUUGGAAAGUCACAAAUGAUUACUUCUUUGAUAUGAUGAACCUAUAAGUCUAUUCAUCUCUGUUAUUUCAUUUCUCAAAUGUGAGCCUUGUUGAGGUCCAUUAUCAAAUCUACACUUUGGUUGAUUAUAUGAUGUUUAGGACAAGGCAGAAUUUAAAACCUGCAUGUUUAGUGCAUCACAUGUCAAGUCACCAUCCUUCUGACAGUGUAACUUCCAUAACGUUAUUUUGAGAGCCAUUUAAUAAUCAUAUUUGAAAAAGUGGAUUUCUUGAGUCUGUUGUAGUUUAGUACUUACAGCAGUGCCUAAAACAGCAACUAAUAUGAACUGCCUGAGUCCUACAACAUAAAUGCAUAAAGCUUUUUUAUGUAAAAGCCACAGGAGGGGUUCAAAAUUGAACUUUUCCAAAGUUUAUUUCUCUUGCGUUAGAUGAAAAACUAUUUAAAAGGACUGAAAACCCUGAGCUUUUUGCUCGUCUUGGUAGCAGAUAUCUGUAAAAACCUACCCAGAAUUGUGAUUUUACUUCAUUGUUCUUGCAUCCUUGAGGCUACAGUAUAAAUCAUCUCCAAACUUGACUACUAUUGGGAAGAUGUGUAUAAAAGCAUCGCUUUGGGAAUUUUUUUAAAAAUAUGCAAAAAUAAAUAUUGAAUAAAAUCUACAUUACCAUAAAACACCCAAAAAUGCAGUUCUAAAAUAAAAUUGGUCACAAUUAAA